ACUCACACACACUCGCUCGCACACGCACACACUCGAUCCAGCACGCGCGGGCGGCGCGGGGCGGCGGCGGCCGGAGUCUGCGGUGCGAGGCGCCCCCGGCCCGGCGCGGCGGCGGAGCCCGGCUGGCGGGGGAGGGGAGGGGGUUGCGGAGGGGGCGGGGUGGGGGCCGGAGCCGCUUGAGCCGGCGGGAGCGGGCACCCCUGCGCGCCGCGCUCGGCCUCGCCUCCGCGCCCCCCGCGCGCCCGCCGCGGUCCCUCCCCCGCGCCCGUCCGCUCGCCGGGCCCCCGCCGCCGCCCCGGGGUGCAGCCGAGCGGCCGCGCCGGGUCCCCGGGACGGGGUGGAAGUGGGGGUGGGGGGAGGGGAUCGGGGCCGGGCCGGGGCCGCGCUGCCUGCGAUGCCGGGCGCCCGCCGCAGCCGCUGCCGCCGGAGCCCGGGAUGGGGCGAGAGGCUGCGGCGGACGCCAGCAUCUCCCCGCCGGGGACCCCGGGGGCCGCGGAGCCGCCGCCGCCGCUGCUGCCGCCGUUGCUGAGACCCAGCGGGCGAUGGGAUGAAGAUGAGACGCUACAAGCUCUUUCUCAUGUUCUGUAUGGCCGGCCUGUGCCUCAUCUCCUUCCUGCACUUCUUCAAGACCCUGUCCUAUGUCACCUUCCCCCGAGAACUGGCCUCCCUCAGCCCUAACCUGGUGUCCAGCUUUUUCUGGAACAAUGCCCCGGUCACGCCCCAGGCCAGCCCCGAGCCAGGAGGCCCUGACCUGCUGCGUACCCCACUCUACUCCCACUCGCCCCUGCUGCAGCCGCUGCCGCCCAGCAAGGCGGCCGAGGAGCUCCACCGGGUGGACUUGGUGCUGCCCGAGGACACCACCGAGUAUUUCGUGCGCACCAAGGCCGGCGGCGUCUGCUUCAAACCCGGCACCAAGAUGCUGGAGAGGCCGCCCCCGGGACGGCCGGAGGAGAAGCCUGAGGGGGCCAACGGCUCCUCGGCCCGGCGGCCACCCCGGUACCUCCUGAGCGCCCGGGAGCGCACGGGGGGCCGAGGCGCCCGGCGCAAGUGGGUGGAGUGCGUGUGCCUGCCCGGCUGGCACGGACCCAGCUGCGGCGUGCCCACUGUGGUGCAGUACUCCAACCUGCCCACCAAGGAGCGGCUGGUGCCCAGGGAGGUGCCGCGCCGCGUCAUCAACGCCAUCAACGUCAACCACGAGUUCGACCUGCUGGACGUGCGCUUCCACGAGCUGGGCGACGUGGUGGACGCCUUUGUGGUGUGCGAGUCCAACUUCACGGCUUAUGGGGAGCCGCGGCCGCUCAAGUUCCGGGAGAUGCUGACCAAUGGCACCUUCGAGUACAUCCGCCACAAGGUGCUCUAUGUCUUCCUGGACCACUUCCCGCCCGGCGGCCGGCAGGACGGCUGGAUCGCCGACGACUACCUGCGCACCUUCCUCACCCAGGACGGCGUCUCGCGGCUGCGCAACCUGCGGCCCGACGACGUCUUCAUCAUUGACGAUGCGGACGAGAUCCCGGCCCGUGACGGCGUCCUUUUCCUCAAGCUCUACGAUGGCUGGACCGAGCCCUUCGCCUUCCACAUGCGCAAGUCGCUCUACGGCUUCUUCUGGAAGCAGCCGGGCACCCUGGAGGUGGUGUCAGGCUGCACGGUGGACAUGCUGCAGGCAGUGUAUGGGCUGGACGGCAUCCGCCUGCGCCGCCGCCAGUACUACACCAUGCCCAACUUCAGACAGUAUGAGAACCGCACCGGCCACAUCCUGGUGCAGUGGUCGCUGGGCAGCCCCCUGCACUUCGCCGGCUGGCACUGCUCCUGGUGCUUCACGCCCGAGGGCAUCUACUUCAAGCUCGUGUCCGCCCAGAAUGGCGACUUCCCACGCUGGGGUGACUACGAGGACAAGCGGGACCUGAACUACAUCCGCGGCCUGAUCCGCACCGGGGGCUGGUUCGACGGCACGCAGCAGGAGUACCCGCCUGCAGACCCCAGCGAGCACAUGUAUGCGCCCAAGUACCUGCUGAAGAACUACGACCGGUUCCACUACCUGCUGGACAACCCCUACCAGGAGCCCAGGAGCACGGCGGCGGGCGGGUGGCGCCACAGGGGUCCCGAGGGAAGGCCGCCCGCCCGGGGCAAACUGGACGAGGCGGAAGUCUAGAGCUGCAUGAUCUGAUAGGGUUUGUGACAGGGCGGGGGUGGCGGCGGCCCCUAGCGCUAUCUCCCUGCCUCCUGCCGGCUCCUUGGUUCUUGAGGGGACCAGGAGUGGGUGGGGAGUGGGGGUGGGGGUAGGGUUUCCCUACUGAAGCCCUUGUGAAUCAAGGGUCAGGCCUUUGAGCUCAGAAAAUAUCCCUCCUGUUGGGAGAGGGCGCAGGCCGUGACGUCUGGGUGGCCCUUAUGACUGCCAAGACUGCUGUGGCCAGGAGGUGCCACUGGAGUGUGCGUGGUGGUCCCUGGGUAGCGGGGGAGGGUAGGCAGGAUUGGGGAAGAGAGCCUGCAGGAUCUCACCAGGCAGCCUCUGGGGGGUGGCCAGGCCGGGAAAAAGCCCACCAUUUGGCAUCCCUGGGCCUUGGGCUCCGUGUGGGAGACCGGCCUGCCAGGAGGACCCAGGGCUCUGUAAGUAGAUGCAUUUGGGUCCAGGAGGAAGCGUGGACACCUCGUAGGGAAGAGAUGAAAAAGCCACAUCCUACCAAGAGGAGGUGCUGAGGGAUGCUUUGCAGUGUAGUCAGAAGUGCUGGGCCAGAUGGAGACAGAACUCCACCCCCUGCCGCAAAGGACAGGACCUGGCUGCCCUGGGAUGCUGGUGCCUGAGUCUGUCUCUGUGCACCCCUCAGGCUGUCGUGAGCCAACACAGGGGCCUGGAGAACCCUGAGGAGCUUUCCUUUUGGUUCUAAACCCGGCGUUGACGUUCCUUCUCCCUUUCACAUUGCUGUCUUGUGGACUGUGCACUCAGUCCUUGCAAGGCCAAGAGUCCAGUUGUAGGUGUGGCCUUGAGGGGGAAGUGGGGAGGAGAAGACUGACAUGAGUCCUCUGCACGGAUCCGUCUCUCCCUCCCCAUCACCCCUUCCUUCUGACACCCAGUCCCAGCUGUCCACUGUCCCAGGUGCAGUCACUGUUGUGCCCUUCCUUGGGGCAGGCUGGCUGGGGGCCAGAAAGGGGCCAUGAGGCUGUCUUGGGCCCAAAAAGGGACAAUAAGGCCAGUUGUAUGCUUCCUGUUCCUCAUAGCUUGCCUUGGUGGGGAUGUCUUUGUUGGAGUUGAUUCUGAGCUGCUGUGAUUAGGAGACCCUGAAAUACAGUGGUUUAAGCAAGAUGGAAGCUUGUUUCUAAUUAGUCUAGAUUGAGAUGGCCCAGAGCUGGUAGGGCAGCUCUGCGUUUCUUCAUACGCACCUUCCAAUUCUGGGUACACAGCGGCUGCUCCAGCGCCCACCCUCCUGUGUGCAUCCAAGCCUGGGGGAAGCAGAAAUAGACAAGAGGGCACACCCACUUUUUGCUAAAGGCAUGAGCCAGAAUUGGCAGGCUCACCUCUGCUGGCCUCUCAUUGGCUGGGACUCAGUCACAUGGCCACAAGCAGCUGCUAGGGAACCUGGGAAGUGUAGUCUUCAGCGGGGCCGCCAUGUGCCUGGCCUCACCUUGGGAGUUAUCUUAUUGAUGGAGGAGAAGAGAAUGGAUAUGGGGGACCAGUAGCAUCUCUGGGAGAGGGGGAGGGAGCAGCAAUAACUCAGUCGUCGGAUCCAGCUCUCAUUGUCAGAGUUUCCGGAACAGCUUGCUCCUGUUUCCCUCACUGUGCAGCCCAGGGCUGGGGGCAGUGAGGAGCUUGCAGCUCUGUGGGAAGGGGAAACACCCCCUCCCCUCGGCCCCUCAGACGCUACCCAAUGAUGCCGGUUUGCAGAGUUGGCCUGUGGAAUGGCUCAUGUUUGUGCGUGUGUGUGUGUAUAUUUAUGGGCAUGGGUGCAUGCUUGGUGUGUAUUUGUACAUGUCUGUAUUGCUGUGUCCCUGUAAAUACAUGCUUGUGUAUGGAUGGAAGAGGCCAGGCCCAGGCCUGGCCUCUUCCUCGGGCCUGUGGCCACACCUCCUGCAGCUCCCCAAAAUGACUGAGGCAGAAAGCCCUUGGGGAGCCUAGAAAGCAAAGCUAAAGGGGAUGCAGGGUCUGUCUGUCUGUCUGUCUUUCAGUCUGAGGAAUGAGAAUCCUGACCUGAGGGCUGUGCAGCUGAGAGCCCACUACCUCCCCAGCCCCUCUCGGCCCCAGCCGCAUCAUCCCACCUGUCCCCUCCCCCCCACCUCCAGUGGGGCUUUCUCCAGAUGUCUUAUGGUUGGGGGUUUCCUGAUGGGCCAGGAGAGGAGGGCAUCUUCUUGCGACAGCACUGUCUGGGUUAAGUGCCCAGUGAGGGCAUGGUGUGGGGAGCUGGCCUCAGAGGAGCCGCUGGUGGGCAAGCGUGAAGUGGGCUGAGGGGCUCUGAGCCACUUUGCUCCCAUCUAGGGGACUGCCCCCCAUGGAACUCCUUUGAAGUCACAGCAGCCUUCCUUUCUGUUUGCUCUUGGGGCUGAGAGGUGGCUCAAACACUCGGGGUCCCUAUGGCUCUGGGUCAAUCUAGGCCAGGCUGCACCCCAUGGACAGGGAGUCUCAGGGCUCCUGAUCAUGCCCAGGCCCUGGCCUGGGGCCUCCCUCCUUGGCAGCUUUCCCACCCCCACGCCCCUGGCAUCCUCAGUUGCUAUGGGAUGCCCCUCCAGGGCACCAGCUCAGGGCUAAGCGAAGGAAGAUAGGAGCAGCUCAGAGCUGCCAGGCUCUGCCUUCCUCACAGACCUGGUGGGGCAGGUCCUGUUCACAGCAGCAGGAGUGAAGGCCUGGCCAUCGGUGGAGAGGGCAGCUGUCAGAGGGCUGGGGGCCAGGGCACAGGAUUGAAGAGUUUCACAUAUCAUCACAGCAUACACUGGGAAUUUGGUGGGGGCAGAAGAACCCAGGGCCACUCCCUCAAUAUGAAGGGAAACCAAGCUGAAUGUGACCACCGGCACACUGCUGCCAUGUCCCAUGUCCACCUUUCUCCCCGGGAAUAACUGGCCCUGAGACCCCUAGACCCAAGGAGGCCUGUCCAUGCCAAGCAUCCGGGAAGCAUGGCUGGCCUUAUCCACCCAUGGGUCACGUCGGUUCCCAGGGGCAGCAUGGGAGAUCUUUGGGGGCAACAGGGAGAGUCUGGGUGGGGAGACGGGACUUGUCCAAGCAGAAGGCAGGACCCUGGGAAAUGCAUAAUGUAAGGACAUCAAUAAUAGUAUUAUUUUUUUUGUAAGGGAAAAUCAAUAUGUACAUUCUGAAAUCAUUUUCUCUGUAAAUGGUUGGAUUUCAUUUCACCCUUAAAGGGAUGCUUAAAGGAGAAGAUAAUAUUAAUAAUAAAAACAGCUACAAAGUCUGAA